GACAGAGCGGACCCAGGCCCUCGGCCGCCCCGCGUCAUGGCCGCGCCGGCCCCGGUCACGCGGCAGGUUAGCGGCGCCGCCGCCCUGGUCCCGGCCCCGAGCGGCCCCGACAGCGGGCAGCCCCUGGCGGCCGCCGUGGCCGAGCUGCCGGUGCUGGACGCCCGCGGGCAGCGGGUACCGUUCGGCGCGCUGUUCCGGGAGCGCCGCGCCGUGGUGGUGUUCGUGCGGCAUUUCCUGUGUUACAUCUGCAAGGAAUACGUAGAGGAUCUGGCCAAAAUCCCCAGGAGUUUCUUACAAGAAGCAAAUGUCACCCUUAUAGUGAUUGGACAGUCAUCCUACCAUCAUAUUGAGCCUUUUUGCAAGCUGACUGGAUAUUCUCAUGAAAUCUAUGUCGAUCCUGAGAGAGAAAUUUAUAAAAGAUUGGGAAUGAAAAGAGGUGAAGAAAUUGCUUCCUCAGGACAGAGCCCCCACAUAAAAUCAAAUCUACUCUCAGGAAGCCUUCAGAGCCUGUGGCGGGCAGUGACUGGCCCUCUCUUUGAUUUUCAAGGAGACCCAGCUCAGCAAGGUGGAACCCUCAUUUUAGGUCCAGGUAACAACAUCCAUUUUAUACACCGCGAUAGGAAUAGGUUGGAUCACAAACCUAUCAACUCUGUUUUACAGCUUGUAGGAGUUCAGCAUGUGAACUUUACAAACAGACCUUCAGUUAUCCAUGUGUGACUUAAAAUGCACUCAGUCACUUUCAACUGGACCUUCUGGAAUGUGACCUUCAAUGCCUGGGUGUAAUAUCCUCGUGCAGUGUCUAACCUGCUGUCCCUUCCCAGCCUUUGAGGAGUUAGGGAAGCAUAAAGGGGGCUUGAACCUGUUGAAUUGCAUGCUGGGAAGCAUCAGUUGUCAAAAUAUGUUAUAUACUUCCAUUUUAUAACUUUUAACAUUUUAUACAAAAAAAAUGAAUAUACAAAAUAUAACUUUAAAAGCUAUAAAAUCAUAAAUACUCUAAAUUAUUUUACAUUAUGGUAUAUUCAGUCAAUGAAAGAGUUUUUUGGCAAUAUAAAUUCUGACAGUAUAUAAGGGGACAGGAGAACAACACAAGACCAUUAUAUUCAGUGAAGAAGGCAAAAUAUCAAAUCUGUCAACAAUGUAACUGCAUUUUUAUAUGUAUAUAUUUGUAUUUUUGUAUGCUUUGGAAAAAGACAGGAAAUAAACACCAAAAUGUUGCCAGUAGGUAUCUCUGUGUUAAGAUUAGUGUUAUUAUUUUCUUUUCUGUACUUUUCUGUAUUUCCCAACUGUUAUAUAAUGAGCAUGAUUAAUAUUGUAGGGCCAGGAAAAGGUCUUUAAACAUUAUAGGACAAUUUUAUGCCACAUAACAACCUUCACAAAAGAGCAAAAUUAUAUAAGCUGUAGUCCACUUUUCCAUCGUAAUUGCUUUACUCAGAGGAAGUGUGGCAAUCCGAACAUUUCACAUAUAGCCAGUGUCCACAGCACCUUCUCAAACUACAUACUUGCUAUCCGUUUCACUAGGAUUUUGGGGGGUUGGGGGAGCUAUGGAGAAAAAAAUUGUUUUAGAUAUUUAAGAUAUGUAUUUAAAAAUAUGGUCAGUGUGCUUUUUGAAAGGGAACUAUAAGAAUUUUUUUUUUUUUUUUUUUUGAGAUGGAGUCUCACUCUGUUGCCCAGGCUGGAGUGCAGUGGCAUGAUCUCGGCUCACUGCAAGUUCCGCCUCCCGGGUUCACGCCAUUCUCCUGCCUCAGCCUCCCGAGUAGCUGGGACUACAGGCACCCACCACCACGCCCGGCUAAUUUUUUGUAUUUUUAUUAGAGACGGGGUUUCACUGUGUUAUAACAGCCAGGAUGGUCUUGACCUCCUGACCUCAUGAUCCGCCCACCUCGGCCUCCCAAUGUGUUGGGAUUACAGGUAUGAGCCACCUUGCCUGGCUUUUUUUUUUUUUUUUUUUUUUUUUUUUUUGAGAUGGAGUCUUGCUCUGUCGCCCAGGCUGGAGUGCAAUGGCUCAAUCUCAGCUCACUGCAACUUCCGCCUCCUUGGUUCAAGCAAUUCUGCCUCAGCCUCCCAAGUAGCUGGGAUUACAGGCACCCGCCACCAUACCUGGCUACUUUUAGUAGAGACGGGGUUCCACCAUGUUGGCCAGGCUGGUCUCGAACUCCAUACCUCAGGUGAUCCGUCUGCCUCGGCCUCCCAAAGUGCUAGAAUUGCAGGCGUUAGCCACCAUUCCCGGCCAAGAAUUGUUAAAAUUUUUUAAAACUUGGUAACUUAAAUGUACACUAUGGUUUAGUUAUGCAUUCCUAGAGAACUGCUAUUUCUCACCCUCAAACUGCUCUUAUUUGGGAGACUUGUUAUCUUUCAUUUUUCUAGAAUUUUUUUUUUUUUUUUGAGACGGAGUUUCACUCUUGUUGCACAGGAUGGAGUGCAAUGGCACGAUCUCGGCUCACUGCAACCUCCACCUCCCGGGUUCAAGUGAUUCUCCUGCCUCAGCCUCCUGAGUAGCUGAGAUUACAGGCAUGCGCCACCAUGCCUGGCUAAGUUUCUAUUUUUUAGUAAAGAUGGAGUUUCUCCAUGUCGGUCAGGCUGGUCUCGAACUCCCGACCUCAGGUGAUCUGCCUGCCUCAGCCUCCCAAAGUGCUAGGAUUAUAGGCAUGAGCCACCGCGCCCGGCCUAUUUUUCUAGAAUCUUAAUAUGUUUAGUUGGGAGGUGUCCCAGAAAUCCUGAUGAAAAGUAUAGCAAAAUCAGAAUUUUGGUAAUGAUUAGCAAGUAUAAUACUGCUUUGAACUCAGUACUUUUAUAUGAAGCAUAUAAAGUUACAAAAAAAACUAAUGUAUUCAAAUAUUUGAAUAUAUCUUCAUGUUUGUAUAAUGUUUUUAUUCAAUAAAAAUGAAAUUUCUCAUUUAAA